AUAAGUAAAUAUUUUCUUUUUUUAAAAAAAGGAAAUAUUCUUGAAUGCAUUUUUCUGGAAGCCUCCUCCUGGUACCUCAGAAUUCUGCUUCCUGGAAUCUCUGGCAGGUAGAAAUGACCAUAAAAGUUUGAUUCUACUCAAGACUUUUUUGGUCAUGGACUAUGACAAGCCACAUUGCUGAUUGCAGACCCUCAACAUUUUAGAAUAAAAUAUAUAACUAAAAAGAUUUAUGACAGGGUGUGUCUCUCCCUCUGUCUUCUGUUCAGAAAAUUUACCCAUUCUCAACAGCCUUGCUUUCCCUCUGCAAUCUGGGCAUUGCUUCCGUCAGUGGUGUCUUCACAUGGAAUUGGGGAAUUGGCAGCUUUUUUUCCCCUUUCUUCAGAGAUUUAAAGUAAAUGACACCUUAGAUCAGAUAGAUGAGCAUCAUCCUUCCUCCUCCCUUCCUUUUUGGAUAGAUUUCAUCUUCAUCUCUCUUGCCCUUCUCUCUCUCAGUCUUUCAAGGUUGCUGAGAGCUCAGAGGGAAUGGGAUUGAUUUCACAUGAGACCUUACUAUUUAGGGUCAUCCUGAACCCAUGCGAAGCAUUUUCUUUGCAGCAGGACAGAGUGCCUGGAUUUCUUCUUCUUAUUGUUAUUUUAUUAUUAUUCAUCUUUACCUGAAUGCAGAGGCUCAUUCUGGUGAACACGUGCCCUAUUGGGAGUUGGUCUUGCUGGACUUCUUUGAUGGCUGGACCCCUGGCUUUUUCUCUCAAGGUUAUAAGAGCCGGGCUUCUGGGUCAGAUGAUGCUUUCUCUGUGGAGGCACAAUCACUCUCUUCUUUUCUGGCUCAGUGUUGAGGCCUCCCGUGCUCAGCCGUAGAGGUCAAUGCUACAGAGCUGACUGAGGCAGGAGGCAAGGCUGAGCCUAGGAUCAGAGGGCUCUUGUUCCAGGGCCAGCAGCUCUGCAGGAAUGAGACCAGGCACCAUUGUGUGAGGAUCCUAGGGGAUGUGGAGGAAGGAAAGGUGUGAUCUCAGACCCACCCACAGGGUCCACCUGUGCCCCAUGGGCUCCCCCUGCCUAUACUGCCAUUGACGUCUGAAAGCACAGCUUGUAAUCCCAUAAGGAUUGGGCUUCUGAAUCCUGCCUGGGGGGCCAAGCAGUGGUUUGCUCCCAAGCCCUCUUUCAGCCUCACUGCUUAGGGCAACAUGGUGUAAGCAAACACCAUGAUCCAGGCAAGCCAGACCUUCCUGGAGCCUCCUUCGUUCUGGCUUAUCUCCAAGUGUGUGAUCCCACCAUGCCCUCCGCCAGGGGCCUGUCCACAUCCGUUUCCGUCUUUGGGAGCUCUGGCUAUCCUUUAAAGCCUAUGCAGACACCUCUCCUCCUCCUACCCCCGCUAAGGACACGUAGCUUGCGUCCUACAUGUUUGAGUUACAUUUGCCCCAGUCACCCCCUCCGUGGUGAGGGUAGGGCUCAGAGCUCUCCUCACACCAAGAGUGAGCCCCAGUCAUUGCUGGCUGGGGGAGGACAAAGGCAGCCAGAUAAAGGCAGCUCCUGCAAGGACGGAGAGGCCACAGGCCGGCAUCUUCACAAACUGUGGAUGUACUGUGUCUUCCAGUAGUCAAAAUAAAGAAUAUAUUUGGCCAUUUUCAGACUAUUUAAUACAGAACAGUUUACACACAGAAGAGGAGUGAGGAGGAGAAUGAAUCCCUGCAGCCCUACCCCUGUUUCCACGGUUAUGGGUGUUUGCCAGCACAGGGCUGCCCAGCACUGGUGAUGGGGUCACUGUUGGCUGGCAUCUGUCGGGCAUCCCCGGGGAAGCUGCGCCGGUGCUGUGGCCACUGAGGUCCUCAUAGGGGUUCUGGCCACUCACAUUUCCGAGGUUCUUCAUUUCCCACCUCAGAUCACUGUUUUCAAACUCAGUUUUCAGCAACAGGGCCUUUCUUCAAACUCAUCUUAUCUCCACCCCUAAUGCUCAAAACAGAUAAAGUAGUAUUAGCACAAAUCCAUUACAAGAGUUUACUUUUAUACUAUGUACUUAUAAAAUCAAUUUGCCUAUGGGAAAGAAGCGUAAAACUACCAUCAUGGGUAUUAAGAUUUGGAUUUUGAUAACAUUUAUGUGUUACAAUUUCAUGUAGCUCAAUAUUCUGUUUGGAUGAAAAACAUUCAGAAAUCACUGAGUCACAAAUCACUGAGUCACAGUGCUGAUGAGCGCUUUGACGCCACAUUCCACACUAACGUGUUGGUGAAUUCUUCUGGGCAUUGCCAGUACCUGCCUCCAGGCAUAUUCAAGAGUUCCUGCUACAUCGAUGUACGCUGGUUUCCCUUUGAUGUGCAGCACUGCAAACUGAAGUUUGGGUCCUGGUCUUACGGAGGCUGGUCCUUGGAUCUGCAGAUGCAGGAGGCAGAUAUCAGUGGCUAUAUCCCCAAUGGAGAAUGGGACCUAGUGGGAAUCCCCGGCAAGAGGAGUGAAAGGUUCUAUGAGUGCUGCAAAGAGCCCUACCCCGAUGUCACCUUCACAGUGACCAUGCGCCGCAGGACACUCUACUAUGGCCUCAACCUGCUGAUCCCCUGUGUGCUCAUCUCCGCCCUCGCCCUGCUGGUGUUCCUGCUUCCUGCAGAUUCCGGGGAGAAGAUUUCCCUGGGGAUAACAGUCUUACUCUCUCUUACCGUCUUCAUGCUGCUCGUGGCUGAGAUCAUGCCCGCAACAUCCGAUUCGGUACCAUUGAUAGCCCAGUACUUCGCCAGCACCAUGAUCAUCGUGGGCCUCUCGGUGGUGGUGACAGUGAUCGUGCUGCAGUACCACCACCACGACCCCGACGGGGGCAAGAUGCCCAAGUGGACCAGAGUCAUCCUUCUGAACUGGUGCGCGUGGUUCCUGCGAAUGAAGAGGCCCGGGGAGGACAAGGUGCGCCCGGCCUGCCAGCACAAGCAGCGGCGCUGCAGCCUGGCCAGUGUGGAGAUGAGCGCCGUGGCGCCGCCGCCCGCCAGCAACGGGAACCUGCUGUACAUCGGCUUCCGCGGCCUGGACGGCGUGCACUGUGUCCCGACCCCCGACUCUGGGGUAGUGUGUGGCCGCAUGGCCUGCUCCCCCACGCACGAUGAGCACCUCCUGCACGGCGGGCAACCCCCCGAGGGGGACCCGGACUUGGCCAAGAUCCUGGAGGAGGUCCGCUACAUUGCCAACCGCUUCCGCUGCCAGGACGAAAGCGAGGCGGUCUGCAGCGAGUGGAAGUUCGCCGCCUGUGUGGUGGACCGCCUGUGCCUCAUGGCCUUCUCGGUCUUCACCAUCAUCUGCACCAUCGGCAUCCUGAUGUCGGCUCCCAACUUCGUGGAGGCCGUGUCCAAAGACUUUGCGUAACCACGCCUGGUUCUGUACAUGUGGAAAACUCACAGAUGGGCAAGGCCUUUGGCUUGGCGAGAUUUGGGGGUGCUAAUCCAGGACAGCAUUACACGCCACAACUCCAGUGUUCCCUUCUGGCUGUCAGUCGUGUUGCUUACGGUUUCUUUGUUACUUUAGGUAGUAGAAUCUCAGCACUUUGUUUCAUAUUCUCAGAUGGGCUGAUAGAUAUCCUUGGCACAUCCGUACCAUCGGUCAGCAGGGCCACUGAGUAGUCAUUUUGCCCAUUAGCCCACUGCCUGGAAAGCCCUUCGGAGAGCUCCCCAUGGCUCCUCACCACCGAGACAGUUGGUUUUGCAUGUCUGCAUGAAGGUCUACCUGAAAAUUCAACAUUUGCUUUUUGCUUGUGUACAAACCCAGAUUGAAGCUAAAAUAAACCAGACUCACUAAAUCCUUUCCAAUAAUUGACUGGUGGAAGGAAAACAAAAAACAAAAACUAAAAACCUCUUAGCUUUUCUGCAAUUCAACUUUUUAUUUUUAUUUUUAUUUCUAUCAAAGACGGUAGAGAGAAACAGCUUGAUGCUGUUUCUACAUUAAAAAAAAAAAAAAAGACAGACUGUUGGUCUUACUAAGGAUGUUUUUACCAGCCUGCCUGACUUCUGCAAACCUACCCUGUCAAGGAGAUCAAAGGGACGCAGGUUUCUGUUUAUUCUGAACAAGGGCCAGGCCCCGCGGAGUGUCUUUGGUGGAUCCCAGAUAACUCCUAGGUGCUGCUCUCAGACACUGAGGAGUUGAGCAAAUCUGUUCUAUUCUGCAGAACCCACAGGACAAAUAAGAGUUCUACUAGAAUUAACAGCCCAAAAGAAUAGCUACAGCUAAGUGAAGCCACUUACGUGGGCUUUAAAAAAAUAAUGUGUUAGCUGAUUCACAUGCACUGGAGUUAAUUAGUCUUAGAAAUGUGUGCAUCCAUACAAAUGCACAACAUAAAGUGAACAUAUUCCUAGGCCCUUUCUGCCUGUGUCAGGGCCAGGAAGUAGAGGCUGGGAACUCUUCUGGUCCCCAGUAUGGCAGGCGCCAGGGAGGGGAUGGUGUGGCCCAUCCCUUCUCUGGAUACCUGGCCAGUGGCAGGCAGCAGGGAGGAGCUGGCCGACCCUCAGUGACUGACAAGCCAGCAAUUCUGAGUUCUGGCCUUUGGGAGUCUGCCUGCUCCAAGCCAGUCCACCCCAGCUGCAGCCCCAAAAGCUGGCUCAAAGUCCUUGGGUGGAUUCACUGGAGAUGGGCAACUUAAAACAAGAGAAACUUUAAUUUUUAAACCUAAGUGAUGAUACAGCUCUUCCCUUAGAUUAUCGCCCAGGCUGGAGUGCAGUGGCAUGAUCUCAGCUCACUGCAAGCUCCACCUCCUGGGUUCAUGCCAUUCUCCUGCCUCAGCCUCCCCCCGAGUAACUGGGAAUACAGGCGCCCGCCACCAUGCCUGGCUAAUUUUUUGUAUUUUUAGUAGAGAUAGGGUUUCAUCAUGUUAGCCAGGAUGGUCUCAUUCUUAUUCUUUAAUGAGAUCAGAGGGUAAUUCACCAAGAAAGACCUCUCCUGUUCCAUUGUGUCAUCCAACAACUGCUCAGAGCUCAAAAUUAUAGAAGGCUUCUGAGCCCCUAGAGAUUUUUAAUUUGCUUCUAAUCCCUGAGGUGGGAACAUCAUGAGGGAAGAUUUGAUUUUCAGAGUUAAAUAAAUUGUAUGUGCUUUUCCAGCCAUCUGGCUCACUCAUUUCUGGGUAAUGCACAUGACUUUGUUUGCACUGGAGGAAGAUGGAAGCUUGCGUGUGUGCGGUGUGUGUGUGUGUGUAAGUGUGAGGUACCUUGUGUGUGACAAGAGACCUCACUUACGAGAAAGUUGGUGGAUCAGGACAUUCCAGCCUCAGGCGGCUUGGAGCAGGAUCAUUCCUCAGCAGGCAUUCCUUCCACAUGCUAUGGAUGAACCAUGCACAAGAUUUUCGGUUUUUUUUUUUUUUUCUGUUACAGUGUCUUUAGAAACAAGUAGAAGUGUUUUGAUAUAUAAAAGGAAUGCUUCAUUUCUUAUCAUUAUCCCAAAAUUGAUCCCUCCCACAUUUUUGCUUUAAAAAGAAACCUUUUUGGUUUUGUAUUUUAUACAGGAACACAAAAUGCAAACAAGUUGUGCAUAUUUUGGACUCUCAAAUAACUUCUCUGUCCUUUAAUAAAGUAAUAAUAAGGAAUAGAUGUGCACAUAGUUAGAAAAGUAUGAGUGGUUAAAAACAACAGUCUCCCAUACUGCCUGUUUUCUCUCUCAGAGGGGACCACUAAUGAGCUUCUAAGGGCAUUUCUAGAAAGGAAGAAAAGAAGAUAAGAGGCCAAAGAAGGAGGGACGGGGGUUAUGGAGAGAGACCUUCCCUUUCCAGCACUAACGCUCUGUGAAGGGCGCUGCACCUUGCAUUCUUCAUGUGGUGUUUUGUCUUAGAGGUCGUCCCAUAAUAACAUAUAAAGAUCUACCUCAUUCCUCCUAGUAGCUGCUUAGCAUUCCAUUAUCUCAGCGGACUAUCAUUUAUUUGAAUAGCCUUUUAUUGGUGAACAUAUGGAUACUUCCAGUUUUUAUUUUUAUAUACAAAUCUAUAAUUGGCAUACUUGUACAUACAUCUUGACAUAGUUUUGUGACUAAAACGGUAUAAAUUCCAACUUAGAAAUGGAAUUGCUGGGUUUAAGGCUACAUGUAUUUAAAAUUUUGAUAGCUAUUGCCAGAUUAUCUUCUAGAAACUGAUCGAAGGAUGUAACUCCAUCAAGAGUACAAUAAAAGGCCCAAUUUCUCAGCUUUCUAUAAUAGCACUGGGUAUUUUCAAACUUAAUGUUUUUCCCAAUAUAAUUGGUGAAACAUGAUAUUUACGAAUAUUAUUCUGAUUUUGGUUUAUUUUGUGUAUAAAAUGGGACAUCUUUUAAAAUUUUUUUGUAGUUUUAAUUUUGAUACAUUUAUAUAUUUUACCCAGUUCCUAAUUGGGUUAUUUGGCUUUUUCUUAAUUUGCUCAUGCACUUUGGGACAUUUUUGUCUUAUGUCUUUAAAAUAUUUUUAUCAUUUGUCUUUCGAUGUUAUUUAUUGAUUUCCUUAUUUAUUGGCAUAGAGUUUAAAUUUUUAUGUUGUCAAUUUGUGAGUAUUUUUCUUUGUCGAUCGUGGGAUUUGUUUCCAGUUUUUAAAAGCCUUCCUCAUUCUGAGAUUAUAAAUAGACUUACUCGCAUUUUCUUCUGAAACUUUAUGGUUUUAUUGGUUUACCUUCACAUCUUCAGACUCCCUGGAAUUCAUUUGUUGCAGGACAUGAGGGAAAAAUCCAUACUUUUUCCUCGAAAUGGUGGUCAGCAGUAUCAAUAAAUAUGUAAUAAUGCAUUUCUAAAAUACAGUCAUAGUGUUUUCCCCAGUUGUUCAAAAUGCAGCCUUAUUUGUAAACUAAAUUUCUUUAAGUGUUUGGUUCUGUUUCUGUUCUAUUUAUCUCUAUGAAUGCCUUUCAUUUCUAAAGCAUUAUUCAUACUAAUAUCAGUAUUUUCAAGUCAACACUCCCAUCAACUCUGAAUCUCUCUCUCAUAUGAAUCUUUUUUCAAUUAGAGUCACAAUGAAUUUACAGAUUGAGUCUUCCUAUUCAAAAGCAUGAAAUCUUGUGUUUAAGUCUAAUUUUAUGUAACUUAGUAGUGUUUUAUGAUUUUGUUCACUAAGGUGCUUUGAAUUUAUAGUUUAUUUCUAGAUGUUUUAUCAUUUGGCUAUCAUUUUCAAUAGAAUGAUUUAUUCCACUUUAUUUUCUAUUUUAUCCCAUUGUAUAAGAAAGUAGUUGGUUUUUAUGUAUGAAUGUUAUAAUCAACCACAAAUUGUGAUUCCUACUUGUUUCUAAGGUAUACUUUUGACUUCUCCUUUCCAAUGUGUCUCUUAUUUCUUUCUUGUAUCUAGUUGAUUUGAGAUCAGUGUUGAGUCACAGUGAUUCAGGUGGCAUGCUUAUCUUGUUCGUGACAUCAGUGGGACGUUUUAAUGUCUCAGCGUUUAACUUGUAUGAAGACAUGUAUUUUCCUUGCCAUAAUAAAAAAGUAUCUGUGUGUUCUCAAACUAUUAAGACUCUCUGGGGAAAAUGUAGAUGUUAGAUUUUUGUCAAAGCCUUCUCAGUGUCCAGAGGGAUUAUCAGAAGGUCUUUUCCUUUGCUCUAGUAGUAUGUUUAAUUAUAUUAAUAGAAUACUUAAGACCAAAUCAUUAGUGUAUUCCUGAGAUGUUCUUUACUUAUUAGUAUCAUGACUUUGGUUAUCAAUAUUUAUAAUUAAGAUUCAUCAUUCUACAUCUUGCUUUUAUGUGUUUUUUGUCCAGAUUUAACUUUAUGCUGACUUAAAGGAAGAAAUAUUAUAAAACAAAAACCUCUAUAUUCUACAAUCAUCUAUUGGUUUUGGAUUAUUUUCUGCUUAAGUGUAGAAGAACUAGCUGGGGCUGUCUGGGCCUGCCGUGGUAUAUUUCUGGAUUUUGCUCAUCAGGCAAGUUAGGUCCUCGAGCCCUUCUAGAGUCCAUUUUAAUGACAUUUUUAAAAAUAAAAUUAAUUCCAUCCACUUUUCAACAUA